AGUUUUGCAAUCAAUUCCUGUUCAAAGGCCACCCUACUCUUCCUAUCCGUCUUUCUCCAGCCCAGACACUCACAGCCCCCUGCCAGACCAGGGGACCUCGGAGAGGCAAGGACAGAGGUUCAGGAUCUUCCUCUCCCUCGGGACCCAAGGCCACAAAGGAGAGCUCCGUGGAGAGAAGAAGGCAGAAGGCAGAAGGGCAAGAGGGCGUGUGCGAGAGAGGUGAAGGAAGGAGGCUGAACUCUACUACUACCCUCAAUACUCACACCAAUUUACCUUCUUCUGGUCACCAAAAUAUAAAAUCAUUUGACUCCUGGGGACACAGAUUUGCUGCCACAGAGGCUGAUGGACAACCAGGCGGAGAGAGAAAGUGAGGCUGGUGUUGGUUUGCAAAGGGAUGAGGAUGACGCUCCUCUGUGUGAAGACGUGGAGCUACAAGACGGAGAUCUGUCCCCCGAAGAAAAAAUAUUUUUGAGAGAAUUUCCCAGAUUGAAAGAAGAUCUGAAAGGGAACAUUGACAAGCUCCGUGCCCUCGCAGACGAUAUUGACAAAACCCACAAGAAAUUCACCAAGGCUAACAUGGUGGCCACCUCUACUGCUGUCAUCUCUGGAGUGAUGAGCCUCCUGGGUUUAGCCCUUGCCCCAGCAACAGGAGGAGGAAGCCUGCUGCUCUCCACCGCUGGUCAAGGUUUGGCAACAGCAGCUGGGGUCACCAGCAUCGUGAGUGGUACGUUGGAACGCUCCAAAAAUAAAGAAGCCCAAGCACGGGCGGAAGACAUACUGCCCACCUACGACCAAGAGGACAGGGAGGAUGAGGAAGAGAAGGCAGACUAUGUCACAGCUGCUGGAAAGAUUAUCUAUAAUCUUAGAAACACCUUGAAGUAUGCCAAGAAAAACGUCCGUGCAUUUUGGAAACUCAGAGCCAACCCACGCUUGGCCAAUGCUACCAAGCGUCUUCUGACCACUGGCCAAGUCUCCUCCCGGAGCCGCGUGCAGGUGCAAAAGGCCUUUGCGGGAACAACACUGGCGAUGACCAAAAAUGCUCGCGUGCUGGGAGGUGUGAUGUCCGCCUUCUCCCUUGGCUAUGACUUGGCCACUCUCUCAAAGGAAUGGAAGCACCUGAAGGAAGGAGCAAGGACAAAGUUUGCGGAAGAGUUGAGAGCCAAGGCCUUGGAGCUGGAGAGGAAACUCACAGAACUCACCCAGCUCUACAAGAGCUUGCAGCAGAAAGUGAGGUCAAGGGCCAGAGGGGUGGGGAAGGAUUUAACUGGGACCUGCGAAACCGAGGCUUACUGGAAGGAGUUAAGGGAGCAUGUGUGGAUGUGGCUGUGGCUGUGUGUGUGUCUGUGUGUCUGUGUGUAUGUACAGUUUACAUGAAUGUUCCUCAGGACAUGGCAUACAAUGGCCUUGGAGGUCCAAAUAAUAUCAAGUACAUCUUGGAGAUGAGGGUGCCUGUCCUGGACAGACCUCGGCAUGCCUUCUGUUUCUCCUUCAAUGCUCCUUAAGGCCUAUGUGCUGGGAAAAGGGUCUUCCCUGUUUGUUUGUUUGUUUGUUUGUUUGUUUGUUUUGAGACAGGGUCUCUGUUGCCCAGGCUGGAGUGCAGUGGCGUAAUCUCGGCUCACUGCAACCUCUGCCUCCUGAGUGCAAGCAAGUCUCCUGCCUCAGCCUCCCAAGUAGCUGGGAUUACAGGCACGCACCACCACGCCCAGCUAAUUUUGGUAUUUUUUUGUAGAGACAGGGUUUCACCAUUUUGGCCAGGCUGGUCUCGAAUUCCUGACCUCAAGUGAUCCACCCACCUUGGCCUCCCAAAAUGCUGGGAUUACAAGCGUGAGCUACCCUGCCCAGCCGGGUCUUCCCAGUUUUAACAAAGAGGUCACAGAGCCACAGGCGGAGUUAGGAACUAAAUUGUCUCCUCCUCCCAAUUCAUAUGUUGAAGUCCUAAACCAAAAUGUGGCUGUAUUUAGAGAUGGACCCUUUGGGAGGUAAUUAGGGUUGACUGAGGCCAUAGGGUGAGGUCCUAACCCGAUGGAAUUGACUUCUUUAUAAGAGGAGGAGGAAAUACAAGAGGGCCUCCCCACCCCUGCUGCACACCUACACUGAAGGAAGGCUAUUUGCAGAUGCAGCAAGAAGGCAGCCAUCUGCAAGGCAGAAGAAGAGAGCCCUCACCAGGAACUGAAUAAGUCAGUCAGUCUGGGACUUCCAGCCUCUAGAACUGUGAAACAAUAAAUUUCUGUGGUGUAAGCAACUCAAUCUAUAGUAGUUUGUUACUAUUUUGUUAUAGCAACCAAAGAUGACUAAGCCAGACAGGUUAUGUCACUCGCCAAGUGUCUUAGUCUGUUUGUGCUGCUAUAACAAAAUACCUUAGACUGGGUAAUUUACAAACAACAGAGAUGUAUCCAGAGAUCCACAGUUCUGGAGGCUGAGAAGUCUAAAAUCAAGGCACCAGCAGAUUCCACAUCUCGUGAAGGCUCACUCUCUGCUUCACAGAUGGCACUGUCUUGCUGUGUUCUCACAUGGCAGAAGGGGCAAACAAGCCCCCCUGGGCCUCUUUUAUAAAGGCACUAACUCUAUGCCUAAAGGCAGGGCCCUCAUGACUCUAUCACCUACCAAAAGGCUCCACUUCUUUAUACUAUUGGAGGGGUAGAAGGAACUUCCUUUCUAGACCUUGAAGGUUUAAGAAUUUGAAUCUAUAAAACAAGCUGACAAUAGACAGAUUAACAGGAGAAAAAGCAUAUACAUUUUUUAAUGUGGGCCAGAUGGCAGAAGCUUAAAUAACACCCCAAGCUACAGGAAGUGAGGCCUCUGAUGGGGAGGUAGUGACACAGGCUGUGGGAGGGGGUAGGGGGAGGAAGUCUGUGGUGAGCAAAGUUUGCCUUAUUACACUGAUAAAGUGUAAUUACACUAAUAAAGCUGGAUCACCUGAGGUUAGGAGUUUGAGAACAGCCUGGCCAACAUGGCAAAACCCUGUCUCUACUAUAAAUACAAAAAUUAGCCAGGUGUAGUGGCAGGGCACUUGUAAUCCUAUCUACUCGGGAGGCUGAGGCAGGAGAAUCGCUUGAACCCAGGCUGUAAAGGUUGCAGUGAGCCAAGAUCAUGCCACUGCACUCCAGUCUGGGUGUCAGAAUGAGACCCCAUCUCAAAAAAAAAAAAAAAAAAAAAAAAGAAGAAGAAUACAGUCAUGUAUCUCUUGGUGACAGGGACGCAUUCUGAUAAAUGUGUCAUUAGGCAAUUGCAUUGUAGUGUGAUUAUCACAGAUUGUACUUAUACAAAACUUAGAUGGCAUAGCCUACUGCAUACCUAGGCUAUAUGGGAGAGCCUAUUGCUCCCAGGCUACGCACCUGUACAGCAUGUGACUACUGAAUACUAUAGGCAAUUGCAGCACAAUGGGAAAUAUUUGUGUAUCUAAACAUAUGUAAACAGAGAAAAAGGAAAGUAAAAAUAUGGCAUAAAAGAUAAGAAUUGGCUCUCCUGUACAGGGCACUUACUACGAAUGGAGCUUGCAGGGCUGAGAGUUGCUCCAGAUGAGUCAGUGAGUGGUGAAUGAAUGUGAAGGCCUAGGGCAUUACUGUAUACUACUGUAGGCUUUAUAAACACAGCACACUUAGGGUACACAAAAUGCAUAUUAAAACAUUUUCUUCCUUCAGUAUAUUAGGCAAUAGGAAUUUUUCAAGUCCACUAUAAAUCUUAUCAAACCAUGGUUGUAUAUGCAGUUGACCGAAACAUUGUUAUUGGACACAUAACUAUAGUUGAAAGAAUAAGCAAAAAGUCUAUCUAGGUGUGCUGUCUUGAGCAACUUUUAAUUAUUCUCCUGUCCUGCAAUAUGAGUUAAUCUUCUCUGAUCGAUGUAGAUUCCAGGAAGGGGUGUCCAGGACAAUUACCUUCCUUCUGGAGAAACUUCCCUUAAUCAAAUAAGAGAACUUCAAAGAAAAUCCCUCCCUGUGCUUUGGAAGGGAAGGGAGGUGGGCAGCAGUGGGUCAGAGAUAGACCUUUGUUCUCUUAUUUCUGAGGCCCUUCAGUCUCCUUUAUUCAAAGCACUCAGCAUGCCAAAGCACCCUAUUUUAGGGUAUCUUUUUCUGAGCCCUAAACACUGUGUUGGGGAUGUCAACUGUGACAGGAAAAUAUCUUGGGGCCCCAGAAUCACUAAGGAAAACUCAAGCUUAGGGAAACUUCUUAGGGCAAACCCACCUCCCACUCUAUUCAAAGUUAUCUCUCUGCUCACUGAGAUAGAUACAUAUCUGAUUGCCUCCUUUGGAAAGGCUAAUCAGAAACUCAAAAGAAUGCAACUGUUUGUGUCUCACCUAUCUGUGACCUGGAAGCUCCCUCCCCACUGAACCAAUGUUCUUCUUACAUAUAUUGAUUAAUGUCUUAUGUCUCCCUAAAAUGUAUAAAACCAAGGUAUGCCCCAACCAUCUUGGCCACAUGUCAUCAGGACUUCCUGAGUCUGUGUCACAGUGUGUCCUCAACCUUGGCAAAAUAAACUUUCUAAAUUAACUGAGACCUGUCUCGGAUUUUCUGGGUUCACAUUUUGGAAACCAUGAAUGGAUUCUGGGUGGAGAUGCCCCUGACCCUUGACAAAUCUAUCGGUGCUUGGUACCAGCAUGAGCUAACUUUAUGGCUCAAACCAAUAGGACAAUUUGCUGAGGUCUGAGAGGACUCCCUCCAGAAAAUCCCUGAUCUCUUAAAAUUUGGUAGAGAUCGGAAGUUUAUUUUGCUGUACAACACCUCUUUUUUUGGAGUUUUACUUGCUCCCAACAAGGAAGGCAAGUUUUCCUGCUUUCAUGAUGAUGGAAGGCAGGUGAUGUUUUUAUGGAGUUUCAGCUUUCUUCCAAUGCACUUAGAGCACUCAGAAAUUGUAUAAUUUGUGUGACCAUUGUUAGUUUUGCUUAACUGUUUUGUUGUUUGUUUCUGUCUUAGUCAAAUCUGAAGGGGAACCCUAAAUUACGGGGUCAAGGACUCUGAAGUGGUAGGAAAACAGCCAGCUUAAAAAACUUUUUUUAAAUUUUAAUUACUAUAGGGGCUUUAUUUACAUAACACAGCCAGCUUUUUGCUAGCCAGACCAAACUCAAAGAGCAAUGGCUGUACUUCUGAAAUAGCAACACUUUGUCCUAGCUGAGAUUUGGUAAUAAGAUUUUUUUUUUAAGUUUUUAAAGAAGCUCAGUGGUUGAAAGUCUGCUUAACUGAAACAGUAACAUCCAUGAUGUGUGUUUUGUGCAUGUUUGUAUUUGAAAGGCCUUCAUGUUUUUGUUUCUUGUUUGUUUUUCUCUCCUAAGACCUUGUCUUUUUUUUGUAGCAAAAGUUUUUUUUUUUUUUUUCCUUUUACUUCUCAGUUGACUGAAUUCUGUUUUCACCGGAUUUUUUGACUAAAAUAGCUAUUGCAACAGAGGCUACUCUUGGGUUAAGGAAGAAUGUAGUUUCGUUUUAUGUUUAAUAUCGCUCAAAGAAAAAUAAAAGCAUCUCCCUCUAACACCACCAGACUUUUCCUCUCUGUACCUUAUCAUGUAAAUUUUGCUAUUUGAUUUUCACCUGGGUUGUUUCCUUUAAUGUGCAAAAAUUUAAGGCUAUUUAGCUGACAACUGCCUAGGGUUGUAAAACAGGUUAUCAAGAAUCUGAAAGUCUAAGAUAGGAAAAAAAAGUGGGGGGGCAUUAUAAAUCUAUAAAAUGUACUUCUAUUGGCAUGCCUAAUACGUCUUUAUAUGUAUGUAUGUGUUGUGUACACGAUGUUUUAGUGCUAAAAAUAUGUAAAAGAGCUCUACUUGGCUUAAAGAAAAAUAAAAGUGCUUAAAUCAGAUACUAAAAAAGAAAAGGCUAGUCAAAUGCUUUUUCAAAUUUAUGUAACUUAAGUAAAAUCUUUAAUAAAUAAAGUAGCUUUAAAAUUAUUGGUAAAGUAGUAUUAGAAAUGUCUUAAGAAUUGCCAGCAUACAUUUUUGUUUGCAUUAUAUUAAUCAAACAGUUUUAUACUUAUCCCUGCCAAAUACCAGAAGGUGUCAAAAUUUGGCAUAGGGGUUAUAAAACUAUAAACCCAGCCCAAAACAGAAUGAUCUUUGCUUGUGUAAUUUUUAAUAAAUAAGACAUUGAUAUGGGUUUAAUGAAAACAGCUGCAUCUUGAAUUUAGUAAGAUUACCAUAACUUCUAAUCCUGUGGCUUUAGGCAGUUUAGUCCACAGACAAUAAGGAGGUUUGUUUUGGGAAAGGACUGUUAUUGUCAUUGUUUCGAAGCUGAACUUAAACUAGGUUCCUCCCAAAGUUCAUUCGGCCUAUGCCCAGGAAUGAACAAGGACAGCUUGGAAGUUAAGAGCAAGGUGGAGUCAGUUAGGUCAAAUCGUUUUUCACUGUCUCAGUUGUAAUUUUGCAAUGGAAGUUUCAUAACUUUAAAUCAUGACUAUCACAGUUUUUAUAAAUAAUCUAGGUAAACAAUUAAUAAAAUAACUAGGUAAAUGUAAUGGGAUAAAUACUUAUAGACCAACUGGACAUAAUUUAGAAUAUAAAGUCAUAUUAAAUUAAAUAAUAGAUAAUUUAUUAUUUGGGUAUUUUCCAAUAAAUAUAUCUUGUAGGAAAACAUUGUUGCUUAAAAAAAAGUGUGUCCUUUUUUAAAAAAAUGGUGAACAAGUUUUGUCUAAUUCAAAGCUUAUUAAAAGGUUAUAUAUAAAACAAGGUAAAAGGAACCAGAAAAGAAAAAAAAUGUAAAUAAAGUUAUAAAAAUAAAGAAUUUUUUCAAGGUUAAAAAGCUGAAAAAGAAAUAAUUUUAUAUAAGAAAGAAUUUUAUAUGGUAAAUUUAGUCCUAAAAUAAAAUAACUGGUUGUUUAACAAGGAGGGAUGUUCAGGACAAACCAGAAAGUCCAAGCAUGUCAUGAACAUUGGUGUAAGUCAUGAUAAGAUUUUAUAUAUAUAUAUACACACACACACACACACCCCAAAAGCUUUUAUAUAAUCAAGUUGUCAUAUUAUUAUUAAGUUUUGGUUUGCUUAGGGAAGAAAGAGCUAAUUUUUAAAAAAUCAAGGUUAUUACAUCCAUGUAUCUUCCUGUGUAUGCUUUUAAAGUCCUUGUAACAUUGAGUUACAGGGCUUUAACUCCUGUGUCUGAAAAAUCACAAACACUGAUGACAAUCAAAGCCUCAUCUUAAGGCCCCGUAGAAGAUGCCAAUCAAAAUAAACUGCAUUCCUGAGGCACUAGGCAAGAAAUUAAAGCUAUUCAACUCCUCAAGGCCCAGGGACUAUUGCGGAAGAGGUGGGCGCGUAAGAUUGUAAGGGCCGAUUUUGAAAGAUCCAGUAAGUUCAGUUUCUCUAUGAACUAAUCAUUCAAGUCAAAGGCACACUGAUGCAAAAUCAGUAUAUGGACCCCUGUGUCUGAUUAGCAAGGUUUUCUUGAAGCAUUAACCAACUCCUUCAUAAAGGUUAUAAAAGGCUUAUGGAAGUUAUAUUUUAUAAUCAAGAUUAAAUCUUAUAGUUUGUUUACAAAAUUUUGAAAAUCAAAUGUGAUUGGCUUCAGGCUGUUUUUAUUAGGGCUUCUUGUUUAGAAAGUUAAGUCACCUCUCUCAAAGAAUGAAGGUUUUUGCUUUUUUUGAAAUCCUUGAAUUAUCACUUGGAUUAAAUAAAUGACUUUACGAUGACCUGUAAUUUUAUUUUGUAAUGUCAAGUGUUUUAAACCUUUUGUAUUUGACAAGCUUUCCAAAAUCAAAUUAUAAAUUAUGUAUUUUUCUAACCUAAUUAAUCCUUUAAGAUCUUAGUUUCCCUAAAGUCCUAAAAUGACAUAAUUUGGCUUAUUUGGUAUAAAAAUUAUAUAGGAAGCAUUGUCAAAUGUGAAAUGGUGUUUGGUUUUCUUUGGGCUGUAUUUGUAUAAAUAUGUUAUUGGUGUAUGUUCCAAAAUUAUGUGAAACUCCUAUAAUUCUAAUAUAACUUAGUGUACAUUAUCAGUAAUAAUCAUAAUUGUUAUAUUAAAAUUAUUGUGUGCCACAGAGGUAAAAAAUUUCCUUGUCAGUUUUGUCUUUUGACUAUGGCUGCCUUAAAACUUUUUUCUUCCAUGCACAAUUGUUGUUUUGGUCCUCUUUUUUAAAUAUAUUUUUAUUAUUAUUUUUGAGAUGGGGACUCACUCUGUUGCCCAGGCUGGAGUGCAGCGGCACGAUCUUGGCUCACUGCAACUGCCACCUCCCAGGUUCAAGCGGUUCUCCUGCCUCAGCCUCCCGAGUAGCUGGGAUUACAGGCAUACACCACCAUGCCCAGCUAAUUUUUUUGUAUUUUCAGUAGAGAUGGGGUUUCACCAUGUUGGCCAGGCUGGUCUUGAACUCCUGACCUCAGGUGAUCAGCCCACCUUGGCCUCUCAAAGUGCUGAAAUUACAGAUGUGAGCCACACACCUGGCCUAUUUUGGUCCUCUUUAGAAGGUGGUUUUAUAAUCAGCUGUAAAACUCCAACAGGUGCUCUUACAUGCAGGUUUCUGAUAACUUUGGAGAUUGUGACAUCAGAAUAGAGGGAAAAGUUUCAGGACUCAUGGAGAGCUAAAAUGUUCAUGAGUAUCAAGCAGAACAGGAAUUAACUGCAUAGACUGAACCAAUCUUUUUGACUUUUUGCUUAAAAUGUUUGCUGAUCCUUUGUUUUGUGUUUCAGUCUUAAAACUUUUCUUUUGAGCUAUUGACAGCUUUUAACAAUUUAGUAUACUCCUAUGACAAAAUUUGGAGCAUAUUUGUUUCUCUCUACCUGAUUUCUCCAGAAUUCAGAAACUAUUUGUAAGUAUUCUUAACUUAUGGUGAUACAGUUAUUUGCAUAAGUGCAAUAAGAAUCUGUUCUAAUUUGUAACAGGACACGAUUGGAGAAAUUGGUUGUUUUACUAAGACUUUGACUGGAAUGGUGUGCUUUUCUUUAAGGAAUCAAACUUGACUUAUGGAACCAAUAAAGUCCUUGGAAAAACUGGCCCCAUAUUUUGUGUACACAGUCUCCGUACAAGAUUUCUGACCUGUAGUAAGUAAAGAAUGUCACUUUCUGACAGGCACAUAAGCCCCAGGUUUACCUCAGAACCUCAAGAGGAGAGGAAAUUCACCCAAUUUAUAAGUAUUUGAUGGCACAAAUCCAUGGCUGGGCAUGGCUUUAAGAAAGUCUUAUCUGAGAUUCCUCCUGUGGAACAAAGUUAAUUGGUUCCAGAGAUUCAAAGCCAGAGUUGCUGUCAGUUCAUUGGUAGAGAUGCCAUCACUGGGCAAGUGUUCUGAAAACAUCUUAUCUGAAUAACAGCAGUCCUGGAGAACAUCUAGGGAUCUAGCAAAGCGAGAGAUACAUGAAGGACAUAAAAACGUUUUUAGAAAGUCCUUGGAAACAGUUCUCAUUUCAGACAUGUAAGCAUGAGCUAGGAUGAAAAGUGAUUUCAUCCUGGUAUCUGCAAUUUUCACAUUCAUUAGGUUUCAACAUAUAAACUUUCAGGGGACACAGACAUUCAGACUAUAGCACCAAGCUGUAGAAGCUACAUAGUUGUAGACCAGGGUCAGCAACCCAAGAAGCCUGACUUCCAAGCUGUGCUUUUAACUUCCCCACCAUGUUGCACCUAAAGCUUUGGAGUUUUCCUGUGAUUAGUGUUUUUGGUGUUGUUUUAUUUUUUUUCUUACAGGAACUCUUGCAAGAAGAAAGGACUAUGAGUUCAACUUUAGAGGGAGCCAUGGGGACUAAACAAAAUUCUGAGGCCCCCUCAACCAUCUAAAUGGACUUCCUUCUGGGCCAGGACACUCGAAAAUUAAACCUGAAAGACUGGUUCAGGCCAUGAUGGGAAGUGGGAGUCGAACAUGCCUCAUCAUACCCUCCAGCAUUAACAUCAACACAGACCUUAAGGCUGAUAAGAAGCAUUUACAAUCUAUUCUCUCUGAAGUCUUCUACCUGGAGGCUUCAUCUGCAUGAUAAAACUUUGGUCUCCACAACCUCUUACAACCCAGGCAUUCCUUUCUAUCGAUAAUUACUCUUUCAACCAAUUGCCAAUCAGAAAAUUGUUAUAUCUACCUAUAAUCUAGAAGCCCCCACAUCAAGUUGUUUUGCCUUUCUGGACAGGACCAAUGUAUAUCUUAAAUGUAUUUGAUUGAUCUCUCAUGUCUCCCUAAAAUGUAUAAAACCACGCUGUUCCCCGACCACCUGGAGCACAUGUUCUCAGGGUCUCCUGAGGGCUGUGUCACAGGCCAUGUUCACUUACAUUUGGCUCAGAAUAAAUCUCUUCAAAUA